AGGCCUAGCUCCGGGGCUGCGGCGGCUGAGGCGCGGGGAUGGAGCCCCUGCGGGUGCUGGAGCUAUACAGCGGCGUGGGCGGCAUGCACCACGCGCUGAGAGAAAGCUGUAUACCUGCACAAGUGGUGGCUGCCAUUGAUGUCAACACUGUCGCUAAUGAAGUAUACAAGUAUAAUUUUCCUCACACACAGUUACUUGCCAAGACGAUUGAAAAAAGGAGCAACACAGCACAGUUUUCAGCUACUUAGCCCAUUAGGAAUUCUUUUGAUGCAUCUUGUCAACAGUCAUUUGAAGUUCAUUGCACACAACUGCAAAACAAAAUAAUUGUGGAUAUCUGAGAAUGAGGCCCUUUUCCAUUUGAUAAUAUAUUAACAGAUGUAUAUGAAAGGGAUGGUGACUGGUCUGCAUAUCACAUUUGCUAAAUAAAGAACAUUAUUGACAGGGCAUUACACUCGAAGAGUUUGACAGAUUAUCUUUUGAUAUGAUUUUAAUGAGCCCUCCCUGCCAGCCAUUCACAAGGAUUGGCCGGCAGGGUGAUAUGACUGAUUCAAGGACGAAUAGCUUCUUACAUAUUCUAGAUAUUCUCCCAAGAUUACAAAAAUUACCAAAGUAUAUUCUUUUGGAAAAUGUUAAAGGUUUUGAAGUAUCUUCUACAAGAGACCUCUUGAUACAAACAAUAGAAAAUUGUGGCUUUCAGUACCAAGAGUUUCUAUUAUCUCCAACCUCUCUUGGCAUUCCAAAUUCAAGGCUACGAUAUUUUCUUAUUGCAAAGCUUCAGUCAGAGCCAUUACCCUUUCAAGCCCCUGGUCAGGUACUGAUGGAGUUCCCCAAAAUUGAAUCUGUACAUCCACAAAAAUAUGCAAUGGAUGUAGAAAAUAAAAUUCAAGAAAAGAACGUUGAACCAAAUAUUAGCUUUGAUGGCAGCAUACAGUGUUCUGGAAAAGAUGCCAUUCUUUUUAAGCUUGAAACUGCAGAAGAAAUUCACAGGAAAAAUCAACAAGAUAGUGAUCUCUCUGUGAAAAUGCUAAAAGAUUUUCUUGAAGAUGACACUGACGUGAACCAGUAUCUUUUACCACCAAAGUCAUUGCUGCGAUAUGCUCUUCUGUUAGACAUUGUUCAGCCCACUUGUAGAAGGUCCGUGUGCUUUACCAAAGGAUAUGGAAGCUACAUAGAAGGGACAGGGUCUGUGUUACAGACUGCAGAGGAUGUGCAGGUUGAGAAUAUCUACAAAUCCCUUACCAAUUUGUCACAAGAAGAACAGAUAACAAAGCUGUUAAUACUUAAACUGCGAUAUUUCACUCCUAAAGAAAUAGCAAAUCUCCUUGGAUUUCCUCCAGAGUUCGGAUUUCCUGAGAAGAUAACAGUGAAACAGCGUUAUCGCCUACUUGGAAAUAGUCUCAACGUGCAUGUAGUAGCUAAACUAAUCAAAAUCUUAUAUGAAUAAUUUUGAAAUAACUCUGAAAGAUGGUCAUAUGAUAUUCCUUCAUUUUCAGAGAGUAAUUCUGAAAUUCUGUUUUGAACUAAUUCUGGUGAAAUUUAACUAAAUUAUUUUAAUCUGUCCUUAUUAAGAAAUUUGGAUUUUAUUAAAAAAAUCCAUGUGUUUCAUCAAAUUUAUAUUACUGUAUUUUAUAAAAUACGAACUAUUGUUAUGCUUUAUGGAGAGUAUAUUUUCAUAUGAAACUGAUAAAUAUAUAUGUGGAAUAUUCUUUUUAAAAACAAUUUUAUAAACAAAUCAAGGAGCACUAGAGCUUUAGUGUCUACAUGAGUAUCUUGUGAAGUGUCAUAACAGGCAUAACAUAUUUUUAUGUUAAUUAAAGAAGUUUUUUAUUUCUAAUUUUAAAAUAAUGAUUCUAAUUCUAGCCCAUUGAAUGUUUUACUUAAUUUCCAAUCCUGUAAAUAUUUCUUUAUUUCAUCUAAACAAAUGCAUAUGAUAUGUAAACCAAAUUAUCAUCAUUCAGUUUAUACAGCAGACUGAAGAAUAUGUCAGGAAAAAUAAUCCUAAAUGUUUGAUUACCUCUCCAUGAAGCGGCCACAGAAACUGUUGGUGCACAUUAUCUACAUUUUCCUCAGCCUCUAUCUGAAGGACAAAACUCAUUUUUCCUUCUUCAUUUUGUAUGUACUUUCCUUUAGUUGACUAUUAUCAAAGCUUGUUUUUGUCUUCUCAGCUUCUGAGUUGAAUUUGCCUUUGCACGCUGAGGAAUGUAGCAUGACGUUAAGAUUUCAGGGAGGAAGCUGCCCUCUGAUCCCAUGUCAUAUGACAGUACUCCCCUCCCCCCAGUUGUUCUUUAUUGUAGCAACAUACACUCUCAAUGAACUUUUAUGACUUUUAACUUUCUCUGUCUCUCUUCCUCAGCAGACCUCUUGGAAUUAGGGUUUCUAAUCAAACUAAGUCUUGCAUCAUAAAUUCUAUGGUUUGUGAUAAAAGCAAGUGACAAAGAGAAGAGAGAUGAAAAGAAACAAGUCCAGAAAUCAUAUUACAAGAUUUUAAUUCAAAUUUUUCUUCUUAAAAAUCAGCUAUUUAGAGGUGGAUAAAUUGGAAGUUUGUGCAUUGCUUGUGGGAACGUAAAAUGGUUCAGCUGCUGUUGGAAAACGCUAUGGAGGUUCGUCACAAAAUUCAACAUAGAAUUACCCUAUGAUUCAGCGAUUCCACCUCUGGCUAUAGAUCCAAAAGAAUUGAAAGCAGGGACUUGAACAGAUAUUUGUACACCAGCGUUUAUAACACCAUUAUUUACAGUAGCCAAAAGGUAGAAGCAGCCCAAGUGUCAUCCCAUUCACCCAUGAAUGGAUGCAGGAAUUGUGUUCCGUGCAUGCAGUGGAAUAGUACCAGCCUUCCGCAGGAAGGAAAUUCUGACAUAUGCGGUGACAUGGAUGAACCUUGAGUACAUUAUGCGAAGUGAAAUAAGCCACCCUGUGGGGAUGGAGAAUGGGUAGUUAGUGCAUAAUGGAUACAAAGUUUCUGAUUGGGGUGAUGAGAAAGUUCUGGAGGUGGAUGGGGAGGAUGGUUGCACAACAGUGUGAGUGUACUUAAUGCCACUGCAACUGUAUAUUUAAAAAUAGUUAAAAUGAUAAAUUUUACAUUAUGUAUAUUUUACUGCAAUUGAAAAAAUCAUACUCUAUUACCAAUUUUUCAGAACUCAUAGAUAAAUAUGAAUGUAGGGAAGCUGUAAGCCAGCCCAUAUACAGAAACUAUCACUAUCUACAUUUUUCAUAUGUGUUCAGACAGAGCCUAUUACAAGUCUCAUAAAUUUCAGUAAACAAUCACAAAUUAUUUUGGCACACUUUCAUGUAGGUUCUGUUCACUGCUGAAAUAUUCUAAAUAAAAUGGUUUAGAGUUUUACUGUAACUAUGAAUAAUUAUGCUAUAAUUAUAGUAUCCCACAUUCGGUUGAGCAACAUUAUACAAAAUAAGUGUCGAGUUACUGUGCACCAACUAUAAAUACUUGAAAGGUCUGUAGAGACAUUUGCUUACAAACUGGUAGACAGAAUGUAGCUUAGUGGAAUUCUUAAAUUAUGGGAAUGUAUUCACAGGAAGACGGUGAUUCUUGCCCUUAAUUCAUAAUUGAAAAUAUGCAGUAACAAGCAUAAAACUCACAUCUUAAUGAAGAUGUAUCUACCAGUGUCAUUCAAUUAGCAGAUGUAUAUGUAUGCAUAAUUAAUUUGGAAAAUGUUAUUUUAUGGAAUGUCUGCUAUAUGCUUUUGGUAAUAAUGCUGUAUAUAAAAUUUGCACUGGAAAUUCUGUUUCCUGAUAUUUGGACUUGUACAUUUAUUCAGAUGUUGGAAAACAUAGCUUCUCAUUUUCAGGAGAACUAUGUGUAAUUCAGUCUUCACCAUACCUUACAGUAAACCGAUUUUUCGUUCUCCUUUUCCCAUCAUCCCUGCUCUUUUAAACGGCUUGCCAGAUAAUUGUAAGGUAUUUAUUACCCUGCUUCAUAUUUUUAGUAUGUCUUCAGGAUCCAAAACUAAUUCUAAGAGAUGACCAAAUCAAUUAAUGUAAACAAAAUGAGUCAUAGUUGGAAAAUGAUUUCGAAGAGGUGGGUAGUCAUUGUAGGAGGGGUCAGAGCCUGACAAUCCUCAGUGGCAGGCAAGAAAGAGGAAUGAUGGCAUCACCUUCACAGAGGACCCUGGCCAUGGUGUUCUGUCUGUGAAAUCAGACCUUCACCAUGGGCACUGCCCUAUGUCUGGAAAGAUGAGAAAAUACCUCCAACCUUCAGCCAACUUAUUCUUCCUCAAAAAGGAGAGCCUUCUAAAGAGGCAAAAACAGUAGUUGAAAUUGUGAACAGUGAGGGUCCACCCAGCACUUUUUUAGAAAUUUGAGGGUAAACUGUUGCUUGAAAUUAUCCAACUUUUCAAAGAGGUAAAGUUAUUUAGUAGAGAGGCUUUUAAGUUGCCCUGAAAGGCUGUAUUGCUACCAUGUGGGAUGUAAAAUUGGAUGGGGUUAGAGAUGAGUGCAGGCAAUUCAACGCAUUGGUAGGGGUGGAAGUUCUCAGCAGAAAUCACCAUCUGGGUUUUUGCUCCCAUCUCAACCUAGUUGAGGUCUAGAGUGAUUAAGCUGGAGACUUCUGAGGAGAGAGAAAUGAACUAAAGAUAAAUACAACUGAUUUAAUUUUAGCCAUAGCAGAACAGAACAAAGAAGCAACCACAUUUCAUCUAAUAUCAAGCACCUACUAAAGGAUGCAUUCUGCAGGCCAGCUGCAUCUGCAUCCAAACCAAAGUCACUCUGGUUGCUCUUUUGCUUUGAUAACUUAAGAGUUUAGAAACAAGCGGUUUCUAAAAAAGCCAAGAUAACACAAUAAGGACCAAAUUUUAAUCCCACAUAGACAAAGAGAUUAAAGUGGGUUUUCCUGAAUUGCUUAUGUUAUGAACAGGUUACCUUGUCAUAAUUUGGCCUUCGGCUUGGGAUUCUAACUGUUUUAGGCCACCAGUUAUGACACUGACUUACUAAUAGCUUUGGACUUUGAAACUGUGUGAGGGUCAUAUAGCCUCAGCAGUUUUCUUGUAGCCUGUGAUUGCAUUGAGAUUAUAUAAUUUUUAAAGACAUGGCCUUUGGACCUCUGUCUACUAGUUAAUCUCUUCCAUCUACCAUUCAAAUGUGCUAUAUACAACUAUCAUAUCAGCUUCUUAGCAAGCACUUUUCUGGACCUCUGUCACACCCACCAAGAUGUCUAGUUAUGCCUUUCAUUUGAGAGUUUCCCUUUGCUGUUUUUUUUGUUUUGUUUUGUUUUGUUUUGUUUUGUUUUUGAGACUGAGUCUCGCUCUGUUGCCUAGGCUGGAGUGCAGUGGCGUGAUCUCGGCUCACUGCAAUCUCCCCCUCCUGGGUUAAAGUGAUUUUCCUGCCUCAGCCUCCCUAGUAGCUGGGAUUACAGGCGCAUGCCACCACACCUAGCUAAUUUUUGUAUUAGUAGAGAUCGGGUUUCACCAUGUUGGCCAGGCUGGUCUCGAACACCUGACCUCAAGUUAAUCCACCCACCUUGGCUUCCCUAAGUGCUGGGUUUUACAGGCAUGAGCCACCACGCCCAGCCUCCCUUUGCAUGUUUUUUAAAAAGGCAUUAAGCAUCUUGCACAUGUUCUUUAGUUUCAGUUUGCAUGAGUCAACCUGUGUGCAUCAUUUUCCCUUUCACUAUUUCUUGUCUUUGCUGGUGAAAUUUUAAAGCUUCAGUUUAAAAAAAAAAAGAAAAAGUAUUUUUUGUUGUUGUUGUUUCUAGCUUCCGUUUCUCUCUUUAGGCUGUCUAGGAACAUUUUAAGGUACUCAUGCUCUUCAAAAUCUUACACAAUCAAGAUCCAAACUCCAUCACCAUUCAUGUCUUAGCUUGUGAAUUUAUUUCUUUUUAAAUAUAUUUGUUCAAGAAAUAUGAGCAUGUACAAUGAGCUGUUUUGGCUUUGUAUUCCCCAAGUUCUCAUAUACAUUGGCUUUAUAUUUACCAUAGAUUCUGAGUCUUACUUUCAGCCACAUCCAGCACUUACUGAAGUCUCCCUCAAGUACACCACACUUGACUCCUAAAGCUUCCAAAAUCUCAUUUUUCCUAUAAAUAUGAGACCGGAAAUUUUCACAAAAAUUACAAGAUAGGAACUGAGUUCUCCCAUAGAACUCUUUUCUGAAUAAGCCUAGGGUUUUUUCAUUUCUUUGCUUGUACCUAGCAUGGCUUCAGUGUUUACUUCAAAUAUUUGCUCUGUAUUUUGUUUGCAUUUUGAUUUCUAUUUUUAUCAGGACAGAUUGAAAUUAUAAGAGUGUACAUAGAGAACAUGUUUGUUUAGCUAAAUUAGCUCUAUAAUCAGAUGAGAUCACCUAGAGGGUCAGAGGAUGAGAGUGAAAGAGAGAAAGAGAAAAAGAAGAGCAGAGGCUUGGAGCUGACUUAUCUGAAGGUUCCGUCCUCAGGUCUCUUUCUACCCUUCACUUUUCAUGCCAUUUUUCUUAGAGAUUCUCACCCUUUCCUACAACUUCAGCCAUUUUGCCGAUGACACCCAGAUGACUCUAAAUCUGCUGUUUUCCUAAGUCCUAUUCUAGAAUCUUCAUGCUGGGACAUUUUUAACUUGGAUAUCUUGCUAUUCAAGUUGUAUCGGAUUUGCAUCAAAUUUAGCAUGCUUGCAACCUAAGCACACUCCAUUCUAUAGUCAGUUCCACUCUUGACUUUAAUAUUUAUGGUACGGUUAGUCUCCACAUCUUCCAAGUUCAAGCUUCAUAACCAAAGAUCAUCUUCACCUUCCUUCUCACUCUGCAUUCCAUUGGUCAGCUUCUGUUAAAAUGGCCUUCCUAAGGCAGGCCUCUGAACGAUCAUUUAUUUUUAGGAAAACUUAUAAAAAGUCACUGAGAUUUAAAAACACCCACACAUAUAUUUGCAAUCAUAUUUGUGUGCUUGGUUAAACAUGUCAACAUUUAACAGAUUUGAGCCUUCUAAAUUUAAUCCAGCAUGAAUGUCGUUUUUACUAAAAUAUUUGCUAUUUUACUCACUUAGCUGGUUCCUUACACAAGUCCAGUUAAAUUUCACAUGUGAAAAAAAUGACUGAAAACACUGAAUGGAAUGUGAUACUCCUUGUGUAGUAGAAAUGAGUUGACUUUCAUAUUUAAGAGCUGAUCCUAUGAAUGAGUAGACAAUAAGCUGAAUAGCUGUUACGAUCUGAGUUUUAAAAAUGGAAAAUGUUUCAUGUUUUAGAGAAUGUAAACUUCCACAAGGGCAGAGAUUGUUAAUACGUUGUCCCCCCAGUGACUUAAAACAGUACUGGCACAUAGUAAGCACUCAAUAAAUAGUUGUUGAAUGAGUGAAUGUAGGAACCAUACUGGAAUCAAUAUUGAAGCUACAUAGAAAGCACCACACUGUGGAGUUCAAACAAUGUCUUUAAGUUGUUCUCUUGAAAACUAUUUAAUUUGUCUGUUACUGCCACUUCUUCCAUGCCCAGAGGAACAGCCAAAGUUACUCAAGUCUGGAACACAUGAUUUAAAAAAUAAUUCUGGGAUAGGCUUUUGGCUUUUGGAAAGUAGCGCAAAUAAAACUUUUUAAAAUACUGUAUUCUGACUUCUGGUCUUGACAAGAGAGUGUAGAUUUAUUUCUCCCUGCUCCUCCCUGAAAAGUGUAAUUAUAAACUCUGGGUAAGUAUAAUUAUAAAAUAAUGCAAGAGGAAUCAGAAGGAGAAUUCUGAAAGGUGGGACCAGGAAGACACACUGCGGAGGGACCCCAAGACUAGAGGAACAACAUGGUUCCAAGACAUCUGACCCCUCACCCAACAGAGGAAGGUUACCCAGGCUUGAUGUUUCCCGACCUACAACCACACAAUAGAAGACAGCCCAGAGAGGCUCGUUCCUACAGAAGAGGGAACUGAAGUCUGGUCGGUAAUACCAGAUGAGUCUGGCUCUACCAGCACGGGGGUAUAUCAGGAAUCCCACUGACAAACAUCCAGACCUGAGACUUGUCUUUUGUGCUGAGAGAUGAGCAUCCAGGGGCCUCUGGCAAAAAGCAUCUAACCCAGGAAGAUUUUUUAUUACCCUGAGCCUGAGACUCCCUUCUCCCAGAGAUACCAUGGGACCUGGCUUGGGAGAAAAUCCUUCUUUCCCUAAAGUAGCAUCAUGAAGGACCAUUCGGGAACCCCAGCAGCACCAGAUAAACCAAGCAGACCAAAAUAACACUGCAAAGGCUUUAAAAACUAAAUUACCACUGGACUCAUAGCCCACAAAAACUAAGCCAGGGCUUGCAUGCUAAACACAAAUGGAGUGACUGCCUACUAAAAAUAAAAGAUUAAAAUAAUAGACAAAAGGUUCAGGAUACGAUGUAAAAUAGCCUGUCAUACCAAGAACCAGAAAAAUCACAACUUGAAUAAGAAAUGACAGUCAACAGAUGACAACACUGAGACAAAUCAGAUGUUGGAAUUACUUGACAAGGAUUUUAAGCAACUCUCAUAAAAAUGCUUCAACAGGUAAUUACAAGUUGUCUUGCCACAAAAAAUAGAAAAGCUCAGCAAAGAAAUAGAAGUUAACAAAAGAACCAUUAUGGUAGGUGCACUAUAUGCCAAUUUUUAAGAAUAGAAAUAAAUGGCAGUUAUGUAACUGAAAAAUAACCAAAAUAGAAAACAUUCUGUGGUAACAGAUAAUUUGAUUAGAUCCUGGACAUUUUGUCUGUUACAUUAACUUUAUUUUCAGAAAUUUAAUUAUGAUGUGUCUUGGCAUGAAUUUCUUUCAAAGUGGCAGAUAUUUCAAAGUGAAUGUAAUAUCCUGUUUGGUGUUCAUUCACCUUCUUGAAUCUGUACAUUUAUAUCUUUUGCUAAACUUGAGAUCAGUAGUAGAGAGGAAAUGACAGAAGAUAGAAAUCAGUGAACCUAAGGACGGAUCAGUAGAAUUUACCUGAUCUAAAUGAUAGGGCAAAGAUAGGCUGACAAAAAAAAUUAACAGAGCCUUGGGGACCUGUGGGACAAUAACAGAAGAACCAACAUUUAUAUGUUUGGGGUGCCAGAAGUAGAGGGGAAAAAAAUGGAGCUGAAAGAGCAUUUAAAUAAUGGCUGGAAACAUCCCAAAUUUGGCAAAACCUUAAAAGCAGCUGGAGGCUGGGCGCGGUGGCUGACACCUGUAAUCCCAGCACUUUAGGAGGCGAAGGGGGGCAGAUCAUAAGGUCAGGAGAUAGAGACCAUCCUUUCCAACAUGGUGAAACCCCGUCUCUACUAAAAUCAAAAAAAUUAGCCGGGCAUGGUGGUGCAUGCCUGUAGUCCCAGCUACUCGGGAGGCUGAGGCAGGGGAAUGGCUUGAACCCAGGAGCGGAGACUGCAGUGAGCUGAGAUCGUGCCACUGCACUCCAGCCUGGUGACAGAGUGAGACUCCGUCUCAAAAAAAUAAAUAAAUAAAUAAAAGCAGCUGGAGAAAAAUGACACGUUGCCAUGGGGCGGGGGACACAAUUUGGAUGACAGUAGAUGUCUCAUCCAAAACCAUGAGGACCAGAAGGAGGUGGCAUUGUCAACUAUGAAUUCUAUAUCUAGCCAAACUAUCCUUCAAGAGAUCUCUGUUUUAUCUAUAUAUGUAUCGAUACACAUAUACCUCUAUGCAGCUCUUUACAAUUAUUAGGGCGAGCAGGUAGUUAACAUGGAAUUAGGCUUAUCUGAUAUGUGAAAUAAUCAAAGAUGAAAGGAAGACACCUAACGUAUAGCUAAUGAUUAUAACUGUGAAAUUAUUCAUCUAAAAAUAGAUUGGAAUAAAAUAAUGAUAGCAGUUAUGUUAGAGUAAUAGCAUUUUAAUUUUUCUUGUUUAUAUUUUUCAAUUGAAUGUGAUCUUUUUUGUUGUUUUUGUUUUCAUCAAUGUGGCAUAAUAUUAGUUUUAUCAUUUAAAAUGUUCUUUCUUUCAAAACACUCAGUUUCAAGUCUUUACUGUAGAGUCUGUUCAUUGUAAGCUUGUAAGUUGCUACCUCAUUUGCAUCUUGAUGCUAUGUAAUAUAAUCCCCUCCCCUGCUGACUUUUUUCCUCCAGAGCAGAAGCUACAUCUUGCCCAUUUGUGUAUCCUCAGUACCUUUCUCAGAUGCUGACAGAUAGUGGGUACCUAAUAAAUAAUUGUCCAAUUAACUGACUUAGAUAUGAGUAUGCUGAGUAUGGUAAUAGAAUUGUAGGUUCUUUCAUGGCUUGGGGGAUUGUUUGAAUAAUUCUGUCAGCCAAAAAGAAAAGAAGUGCUGGGCAUGGUGCCUCACACCUGUAAUCCCAGCACUUUGGGAGGUCGAAGUGAACGGACCAUGAGGUCAGGAGUUCAAGACCAGCCUGGCCAUGAUAAAACCCUAUCUCUACUAAAGGUACAAAAAAAAAAAAAAAAUAGCUGGAUGUGGUGGCAUGUGCCUGUAAUCUCAGCUAUUCAGGAGGCUGAGGCAGGAGACUCACUGGAACCUGGGAGGCGGAGGUUGCAGUGAGCCGAGGUCGUGCCAUUGCAUCAUUCCAGCCUGGGUGACAGGGCAAGACUCUGUCUCAAAAAAAAAAAAAAAAAAAAAAAAAAGCACACUAGAUGUUACUGGAAGAAUAUUUAAUGCCAAAAUUGUGUAUAACUCCUAGGGUAUUGUUUAUGUCUCUUCUAAACAUAGUCUAGGAAUUGUUGACAAAGCUUGAUUUAGCAGUACUUCCGUAACAAAUAUGGUCCAAGUCACUAUAAAGAAAGCAUACAAAGGUGUUGUUUUUUAUAGAUCUUAGAAUAACGGCAUUGAAAAAGACAGAAGUGAGGUCAUCUCAUCCUUUCUGCCAUUGAUGACAACACCUUAAAUCUUCCCACAGAUCUAUGUGGCACUUCAAUUAACAAAUCCCCUGGGAAUGAUGCCCCUUUGUAAGGCAUCAGCCUUGUUAAAUCACUCCUCUAACCGUAAAUCACAUCCGUAAUGCAAAGCUUCCUCUCACAAGAUAAAGAUGCCUGUGUGUACUGCUUCUGCGUCUAUCUUCCCAAUUAAAGGUACAAGAGGCAGAGUCUGAAGAGUGCCAGGUAUCCCCAAACUUUGUUUUCUUUUUCUUUUUUUUCAUUUUCCUUCCCAGAAGAGAACCAAACUGUUUUUUUCUUCCCCCCAUCGGUGGUGACAUCCUCACCUCUCUUGCUCUCCUCCCCUAAUAGAACACAAAAUAUCAUCACAAAGAUGUACUUUCCCCUUUUCCUAAGAUCAGAUCCAAUAUAAGUUGUUUGCAGUUAUUUACCACCUACAUUUCUUCUGUCAUUCAUGCUGAAGUCUGAGUGCAAUCAGACAUUUUCCUUUGAUUAUCGUAUGAAUGGUGUCUAAAUAUUUAACUUCACCGCCUUGUUUGGGGAAUUUUAGGGGUCACCAAGUAGAAAACUCAUUUUGUCCUUUUUAGGUUGAUUUGGAACAGGAUGGCAGGAGGGUUCACCUAUGGUAAACUCCGCUUCAUUGCUUCACACCUUGGAAACCAAGCUUGGAUUAAUCCAAUGGAGCUGCUGAAGUCCCCAUUCCGGGAGCUGUUGGAGGUAGAGAAAGCUCUGUUGAUUUUUUUACUAGCUUUUGGAGCCUUUAAUCCUAGCAAUUAGUAUCUCCUCUGCUAUGGCUGAUCCUUAUAAUGAUGCGAGACCCUCCAGUGCAUAUUUUAUGUUUUCUGUAACAUUUGCUUGAGUUACAAUUAGGAAGCUGUGUGUGCACACGUGUGUAUACAUGUGCCACGAACACCCCUGUGCUCCUCCUCCAAAGCCCUAUUCCCCUAUUGCGUUUGUCCCUCUGGAUUUGAAUUUCGUUAUUUUUUUCUCAUUGUUUAUGAAGGGAUUAUAUUACUUAAAAAAAAAAACUUGAAAAAAGUGGAAAAGUUCUCCAAACUCUCAACAAUCUGCUUUCUCAGGAAAAGCUCUGCCAAACCUCAGCAAUUUAAAUGUUAAUGAUUAACUCAUAAUUCUUUUUCAUUCUACUCAAAGAUAAUUGUAGUCAUUGUAAUAAUGAGCAUGGAGAACAAAUGUCUGCUUUAUGUGCCUUGAGCCAAGACCACACUGCUUUCAAAAAGAUCAGUUCAUCACAGUAGUAGACUUGGUAAUUUCCUACAUGGUAAUGCACUUCCCAUGAAAUGAGCAAAAGAAUAGUUUUAAAUGUACCUUGAUUUCCAUCAUUAUUUUAUGUAAUCCUUCAUGGAAAAUGAAAGAAUUGGAACAAUGUUAUAUUGCCCUGAAAUUUUGCAGAAAAUCACAAAACUGACAUAUGUAAAUGUAUCUUUUAAGCAAUGUUACGUCCCUGAAAAAGAGAAUGAAUUAAGUGUCAUGAAGGUUAAAAGAUCGUUAUAUUCACAAAUGUUUCCAUUAAUGACUAAAAACCAGAUUAAUUCUACAGUGUUCUGUUUUAAACUGAUAUGAAAAUGAAAAGGGACUAAAAAAAGCACAAAAGCCAGAUUGAAGCUAUAACAUGUAAUGGGAGCUAGCAUUAGGGGUGUGAGAAUCUUGCCAAUUUGUCCAUCCUCCAACGCACCUCUGCAUCUCAACCCUCUCCUCAUUUUUAUGACUCCCACAUUGAUCCAGUCCUCCAGAUAAAUUCAGCUGGCCUAGCAGAAAUAUCACAUAAGGAUUAUUGCACUCAAGAUAAAAGAACAUCCCCCUAUUAAAAAGAUUAAAUCAACAUUCUUUAACCUGCCACUUAAGGCCUUCUGUCGAUGUCUCUUCCUUUACCCAGCCACUUUCCUUCAAGGUCACCCUGCUGGACAAGUGGAACAACCUUUUUUUUUUUUUCUUUUUUUUUUGGCAGAGUUUCGCUCUGUCACCCAGGCUGGAGUGCAGUGGCUCUCGGCUUGCUGCAACCUCCACCUCCUGGGUUCAAGCGAUUCUCCUGCCUCAGCCUCGCCUCCUGAGUAGCUGGGACUACAGGUGUGUGCCACCAUGCCCGGCUAAUUUUUUUGUAUUUUUAGUAGAGACAGGGUUUCACCAUUUUGGCUGGUCUCAAAUUCCUGACCUCAAAUGAUCAGCCCGCCUUGGCCUCCCAAAGUGCUGGGAUUACAGGUACGAGGCACUGAGCCCGGCCAGUGGAACCACUUUCUAUAGUGUGCCCAUACUGGGCCUUGGACAUCUUUCCUAGUUUGGUACCUGCUGUUUACUUAACAGCAUGCUACUGUGUAUCUGUGCCAUCUUGUCACACUUGUCUUUGUAAUGUUGCCUAACUCUGGCUCUCCAGAUUUGUACAUUACGACUUUAUUGUAAAUCAGAGAAGGUCAAUAAAUUUACUUCUUUCAAAUUUC